AUUCUAAAUGCAAAGCUAGACUGAGCAAGGGAAGUGACAGGAAAUGGAGCUGGGGAGACAAAAAUGUGGAUAACAACAAAAGAAUUUCAACAGGUAAAAAAAUGAGUCAAACAUCUCUCAAACAGAAAAAGAAUGAGCCUGGAAUGAGGUCCUCAAAAGAGAGUCUAGAAGCAGAAAAAAGAAAGGAAUCUGACAAAACAGGAGUUCGUCUGAGCAAUCAGAUGAGGCGUGCAGUCAAUCCGAAUCACUCGCUGAGAUGUUGCCCCUUCCAGGGUCACUCGUCGUGUAGACGCUGCCUUUGUGCAGCUGAGGGAACAGCCCUUGGCCCCUGCCACACAAUACGUAUUUAUAUUCACAUGUGCCUGUUGUGGGAGCAGGGCCAGCAGAUCACCAUGAUGAGGGGAUCACAAGAAUCAUCACUGCGGAAGACAGACUCUCGAGGGUACCUUGUGCGCAGUCAAUGGUCUAGAAUAUCCCGGAGCCCAUCCACCAAGGCUCCAUCCAUAGAUGAGCCUAGAAGCAGGAACACCAGUGCUAAGCUCCCCAGCAGCUCCACGAGCUCCCGGACUCCAUCCACCUCCCCAAGCCUGCAUGACUCCUCACCGCCGCCGCUGUCCGGGCAGCCCUCGCUCCAGCCACCCGCGUCGCCCCAGCUGCCCCGGUCGCUGGACUCGCGGCCUCCCACGCCCCCAGAGCCCGAUCCUGGCUCCCGGCGCAGCACCAAAAUGCAAGAGAAUCCGGAGGCCUGGGCCCAAGGCAUCGUGCGGGAAAUCCGCCAGACCCGGGACUCGCAGCCGCUGGAAUAUUCGCGCACGUCCCCCACCGAGUGGAAGUCCUCCAGCCAGCGCAGGGGGAUCUACCCCGCCUCCACCCAGCUGGACCGCAACUCUCUGUCCGAGCAGCAGCAGCAGCAGCGGGAGGACGAGGACGACUACGAGGCUGCCUACUGGGCAUCCAUGAGGUCGUUCUACGAGAAGAACCCGAGCUGCUCGCGCCCCUGGCCGCCCAAACCCAAGAACGCCAUCACCAUUGCUCUCUCAUCCUGCGCGCUCUUCAACAUGGUGGACGGCAGGAAAAUCUACGAGCAAGAGGGUCUGGAAAAGUACAUGGAGUAUCAGCUCACCAAUGAGAACGUCAUCCUGACCCCGGGCCCGGCGUUCCGCUUCGUCAAGGCACUACAGUAUGUCAAUGCUAGACUCCGUGAUCUAUAUCCUGAUGAACAGGACUUAUUUGAUAUUGUACUGAUGACUAAUAACCAUGCCCAAGUGGGAGUGCGGCUUAUAAACAGCGUCAAUCACUACGGCUUACUGAUUGACCGCUUCUGUCUGACCGGGGGAAAAGACCCCAUUGGCUAUUUGAAGGCAUAUCUUACCAACUUGUAUAUUGCUGCAGAUUCUGAAAAAGUGCAAGAGGCAAUACAAGAAGGUAUUGCCUCUGCGACAAUGUUUGAUGGAGCCAAAGACAUGGCUUACUGUGACACUCAGCUCCGUGUAGCCUUUGAUGGGGAUGCUGUCCUCUUCUCUGAUGAGUCUGAACAUUUUACCAAGGAGCAUGGGCUCGACAAAUUCUUCCAGUAUGAUACAUUAUGUGAAAGUAAGCCUCUUGCUCAGGGUCCCCUAAAAGGCUUUCUGGAAGAUUUAGGCAGACUGCAAAAGAAGUUCUAUGCCAAAAAUGAACGGUUACUUUGUCCUAUCAGGACCUACCUGGUUACAGCUAGGAGUGCAGCCAGUUCAGGCGCCCGUGUGCUGAAGACCCUUCGACGCUGGGGUCUAGAGAUAGACGAAGCUCUUUUCCUUGCUGGAGCCCCCAAAAGUCCCAUCUUGGUGAAGAUCCGGCCCCACAUCUUCUUUGAUGACCACAUGUUCCACAUUGAAGGGGCACAGAGGAAGAGCCUAGGCUGGAUGUCUUGAUCAAUAACGCAGGGAUCUUCCAGUGCCCUUACAUGAAGACUGAAGAUGGGUUUGAGAUGCAGUUCGGAGUGAACCAUCUGGGGCACUUUCUACUCACCAAUCUUCUCCUUGGACUCCUCAAAAGUUCAGCUCCCAGCAGGAUUGUGGUAGUUUCUUCCAAACUUUAUAAAUACGGAGACAUCAAUUUUGAUGACUUGAACAGUGAACAAAGCUAUAAUAAAAGCUUUUGUUAUAGCCGGAGCAAACUGGCUAACAUUCUUUUUACCAGGGAACUAGCCCGCCGCUUAGAAGGCACAAAUGUCACCGUCAAUGUGUUGCAUCCUGGUAUUGUACGGACAAAUCUGGGGAGGCACAUACACAUUCCACUGUUGGUCAAACCACUCUUCAAUUUGGUGUCAUGGGCUUUUUUCAAAACUCCAGUAGAAGGUGCCCAGACUUCCAUUUAUUUGGCCUCUUCACCUGAGGUAGAAGGAGUGUCAGGAAGAUACUUUGGGGAUUGUAAAGAGGAAGAACUGUUGCCCAAAGCUAUGGAUGAAUCUGUUGCAAGAAAACUCUGGGAUAUCAGUGAAGUGAUGGUUGGCCUGCUAAAAUAGGAACAAGGAGUAAAAGAGCUGUUUAUAAAACUGCAUAUCAGUUAUAUCUGUGAUCAGGAAUGGUGUGGAUUGAGAACUUGUUACUUGAAGAAAAAGAAUUUUGAUAUUGGAAUAGCCUGCUAAGAGGUACAUGUGGGUAUUUUGGAGUUACUGAAAAAUUAUUUUUGGGAUAAGAGAAUUUCAGCAAAGAUGUUUUAAAUAUAUAUAGUAAGUAUAAUGAAUAAUAAGUACAAUGAAAAAUACAAUUAUAUUGUAAAAUUAUAACUGGGCAAGCAUGGAUGACAUAUUAAUAUUUGUCAGAAUUAAGUGACUCAAAGUGCUAUCGAGAGGUUUUUCAAGUAUCUUUGAGUUUCAUGGCCAAAGUGUUAACUAGUUUUACUACAAUGUUUGGUGUUUGUGUGGAAAUUAUCUGCCUGGUGUGUGCACACAAGUCUUACUUGGAAUAAAUUUACUGGUACAAAUUCUUAA